ACAUGAGAUUUCGGUGGGGGCAUAGAACCCAACCAUAUCAAUAUAUAACUGUUGGUUGUUAUUAAUAUUAUCAUUAUUGACUGCAUUGCUUUCAGAGUAGAUCAUUCUAGUAGUCGCAAUAAUCUGGAACAGAGGAUUCAGGUAAACUUAGCGCUUAUAAUAAUGUUUGCAAAGGUAAGUAAUUCAUUUAAGGUUUCUUGUUUCGCUUCUGUCACAAUUCUCUUCCCAUGAUAAAAACGGUUAACACUGAUGGAGCCCUUAAAUAUGUAGCAGGUACUCUGCUUAGUGUGGUAUGUGAGUUCUUCAUUUAAUCAGCACAGCCACCUUAGGAACUGUGCACUCUUAUCAUCUGCGUUUUACGGAUGAGAACGCUAAGAUUUAGGAAGCAAGUCAAGGUCAGCUAGUAAGUGGUGUAGCUGGGCCUUAGUGCACGUCUGCCUGGCUCCAGGACCUGAGCUCAUGACUUCUUUGCUGUCUUUUCCAGCAUAAAUACUCAUUGAAUUGGCAGCCUGGAAAAGGUCUUUGAGUUCUGACAUGCAAACAUUGAUUUUCCUUACAGUAUUGUAUUUGUCUCCAUUUCUGGGCAUGAUGGAGCAAGAUAACAAAAUAAUUUUUAUCAGAGGGUCUGCUUCAGCACUUUUAAUGUAUAGGUUUGUGUAUGUAGCUUUUUCUAGCAGCUCAAAAAUGCAAUGUAGAGCAACAUCUCUGUUUAACAUCUAACUUCCGAUCAAGGUGUUUGGCAGGCAUGUUACAAGCAGAAAGUAUGAAUAAGAUCGAGUGUGUGGGUUGCAGAAUAUUAAGGUAUUAAGGCUGGAGUCAGCCAUUCAUGCAUUCAUCUAUCAAACAUUUUUAUGCACCUGUUCUAUGAAGGUACUCUGCCAGACACUGCAGGGAAUACCAAGAUGUGAAGACAGUGCAGGAGAGAGGAAGGGUUUGAGACUUUGGUGGUGGACAACCUGGGGUUUGAAUCCCAGCUCUACUCCUUACUGACUAGGGGGACCUUGUUCCAUUACUAAACAUCUCUGAGGCUUAGCUUCCUCAUGUGCAAAAUGGGGAUAAUAACAUCUUAUAGGCUUGUUGCAAGAAUUAAACGAAAGGUAUAGGUAAGGUUCCGAGCCACCAGGAAGUAGUAGGUACCAACCAAUAGCAGUGUCCGUUUUCUUCUUCUCAUCUGUCUCCUCUCAACCUCUCCCUUCCCUUCCCUCUUCCCCGCUGCCCCCUACUGACAGAGUGGUGGUAGAGAUAAAAGUAUCUAAAAUCCAAGGCCGAGUGUGAUCAGUUCCUUUAGAAUGUCGUUUUCUGGUUCUUCCACCAGAGGCUGGGACAAACCUGACAGCAGUGUAGGGUCCCUGUGACCCUUUGUUGUUACCUAAGCUGGCCAAAGAGGAUGGCCAGGAGGCAAAUGGCAGCUUGGAGCCCAAGAGAGGUACCUAUGGUGUAGAAUAAGGUUUGGGUACAAGGGGUAAGGGAGAAGCUAUUUUAAGAAGAAGUCAAGAACUCAGGUCUCAUGGAAGUUGGAACAAGUCAGAAAUGAAGUUGGAGGUCAGCUGAACAGAAGCGGUUGGGGAUCCAGGAUGCAGGGGGAUAUAAGUGACCAUUUCUUGAGGGGUCCAAGGCUGGGUCAGAGGCUCAGCUGUGCUGCACCAGCUGGAUGGCUUCUGCUAAAAAGCUCAGAGGAGAGCUGCAGCCUGGUGCAUCUCCAGAUUGGUGCAUUGCCUCUUAUGGACUUCUGGCUCCCUGGCCUCCCACUGCAGGAUUUUUCCAAAAGCAGUACAUCCCCUGUCAGUGAGUAGCUAAGUCAAAAUUAUUAGUUGUCUGGCAAUAACUACUGGAGCUCUUUAAGGGGUAGCUAUUGUCACAGGAGAAAUGAGCCUCUCCCUGACCCCCUCUGAGCUGGGGAUUUGGUUAAUUACAUCCAGGUCUGUUUCACUAUGAUGCAGAGAGCCAGAUCCAUGGAGGCCUGUAUAGGGCCCUGCUUGCAGUUCUGUAGACUAGCCUGUGUUGUUAGAUCAGGGAUGGUCUUUAGAGAGAUGUUCCAAGUGGUUUUAUGAUACUGAGCCGCCUUGUUUGGUGACCAGGGUAGAUGUGUGUGGUAGGGAGGGAAAGUGGAUUUUACAAAAUCAUUACAGUUCAGAAACGUCUACCUCAGCCAGGAGCAGGAAGCCUUAACUCGUUAUUUAUUAUGCCAUGGCACAUAGGCAUAAACCAGCCCUUCUGUGAAUAAGCAAACAGAACCUGCCCAGGUGCAAGAGAAGCUUGAUUCAGGCUUUUUUUUUUAAAGCCAAAAAUUUAAAAACAGUAUCGAAUUGGAGAAGAGUUUGUUUCAAGCAAGUUACUGUAAUUUUCAAAAGCCCAUUUUGUGGAACUAAUACAGUGUAUUAAAAUGAAUUGAACAAGCAAACUUAAAAAAAAAAAACACAGAAGGACAGCUUAGUGGGAAGAGGAAUAGUCCUUGAAAUGAAACCCAAGUUAGUUCAAAUGGUUCUUGGGAAUAUUAGUAUCAUGAGUACAUGCAAAGCACACAAAUAAGUGAAAAAAUCUCGGAAUGAAUGAACUGGAUAAGGAAACAGCACCCCUGGUGAAUGGGCCUGGGAGACGGAGUCAUGCACAACGACCUCACUUUUUAACUCUGUGAACUUGGGCAAGUUCCUUAAUGUUUUUUUUUUUUUGAGAUGGAGUCUCACUCUGUCACCCAGGUUGGAGUGUGGUGGUGCGAUCUCGGCUCACUGCAACCUCUGCCUCCCGGGUUCAAGCGAUCCUCCUGCCUCAGUCUCCCAAGUAGCUGGGAUUACAGGCACUCGCCACCACACCCGGCUAAUUUUUGUAUUUUUAGCAGAGUAGAGGAUUCACCAUGUUGGCCAGGUUGGUCUUGAACUCCUGACCUGAGGUGAUCCACCCUCCUUGAUCUCCCAAAGUGCUGGGUUUACAGAUGUGAGCCACUGCGCUCAGCCUACUUAAUUCUUUAGAUUCCUGUUUCUCAUCCAUAAAAUGGAAUAAUCAUGCUUAUUUUACUGAGGGGUUUGCUGAGUCAUUGAGCUAAUGUACGUAAAUGCUACAGCACAUGGUAAAUCCUUAAUAUAUGUGUCAACUGUUAUGGCAGAGAGGGACGGGAAAGAAACAUGGAAAAGAAAACGAGUGUCAAGGAGCAUUGGGAAGAUGAGGAGGAGCAUGCUAUAUUUGCUUUAGGCCUUAUAUCUCCUAUUUCUAUUCUUAGUUUUUUAAAUGUGUAAGUUCUAGAUUAUUAUAAUCAAAUAUAUCUUGAAUACCUACUGUGUACCUGUCGCUAUGAUAAGGUGCUUGGGUUUGGAAACUAAUCCCAGAAAUCCCUUGAUAUCUUUGAAGUUCUAGACUGACAGGAAUGACUAGAACUUGCUGUUAAAGGAUGAAUUCCUAAUGUCCCCUGGCUACUUUAAUUAGUUACCGGAAAGGUAAUAGUUUUUCUUUUAUUAUUUACCAUCUGCUCUUUAUACAAGAGGAUAGGAAAGAAAUACAUCUUCUUGGACCUCCAUACGUAUAAGUAACUUAAAAUUUCCAGGUUACCUUUGAGCAACUUAUAUGCAUAGAAGUAAGAUUUUUUUUGAGUACGUUUAUGGCUACAUAAUGGGUGAACAAGGGAGGAGACUUGUAUUUUGCAGGGAUAUUUCUUUGGAUAUACCUAUGACCUCCAAGUUGUCUAAAGCAUACUUUUUGGCAGGGAGAUUUCUUUCAUCUUUUAACUAAACUUAUGGCCCAUUUAUUUCUGGGCCUGAAUAACAGGAAUAACAGGAGAAAGCUGAGUUUGAGUCUUUAUCUUUCUUUUUUUCUUUUCUUUUUUUUUUUACUUCUCCUCCAGUUGGAGGUGUAGACAAGUUUCUACAGUAGGAAACUAGCUUGGUGGAGACAGAGCUCUGUAGCUGACUCACUCUGUAGCCCUGGGCAAGUUCUUAAUCCAUAAAGUAGGAAUUUAAUCAAAUGCAAAGCAAUGAAAUUUGUGGACUGUGAAUUGAUUCAUCAGUCCAGAGGGUGGCUGAAGCCGAAAUCUGAGCAGAAAAUAGUCACUUUGUUGGAUCGAGUAAGCUGGUUCAACAUUUUGGGUCUGGGGUGCUCUCAAAAAUAGCUUUCCUUAGUAGAGAACAUAUUAUUCACUUAAGUAACUAAAAAUCCUGAGGGUUUUCCCCAUUAAUAUAUCUGGGUAUAAAAAGGAAUUUAUCCAGCUUCACUGGACUUAGCUUUUUGCAUUCUUCCAAGAAUGAGUCUGCACCAGUGCUUGGGGCAUUAUUAGUGUGGAUAACAGAGGCCUCAGGGAACGCCUCCUUAGACCCUGUAUGUAGAACCAGUAUCUUCACGUUUGGUGUUCUAAUGGAAAAUGAAGUUGGAAAUACCGGCUUUUUUUUUUGCUUUCUCUCCUACUCAAGACAUUGACCUCUUGAACCAACUGCAGGAAUUAUUUGCUGGCUAAGUACCAGGACUGCAUUUUUCCCCUGUCGUCUCAAGAUGAUGAAUUUUACUGGUGCACAGAGGGUAACCAGUGACUUUUUGCACUUUUCACCAAGGUGGGAUGGGAUGUGAAUGUGGGACCCUUGUAAAAUUGUCUGGUUGCUUGAAAGCAUGAGGAGGGGCUUCUUUGGCUUGUGGAGCUGGCCACCCACUAAAGUGAAGGCAUGUGGGAGGCAUUGGCUCUUUAAACCCCUUUCCCUGGUGUCCACAAGCGAUGGUUGUGUUAUUCUUGGGGCAGAUGACAUGCCAGUGUGUGAAACCACCAAGUAUCGCCCUUGCUCUCCAUCGUGUAGGAAAGAAGGUCAGAGAAUGAAUGGCAAAGCUUUGAAUAAAGCUGAUCGUGUUUGUUUAUUUAAUGUACAUGAGCUAGAAAUCUUUGAAAUGGCAAAAUCAUGCAUUUGAAAGAGAUACUUCAUUUCUGGAGGACUUGUAGGCUUCAUUUAAUAAUCUUGUCAAUAACAUGUUGGAGUUGGAAUUAAUGAGAGAACCAAUGAUUAGCAAAAAUAUAUCAACAGAAAUAAUAGCAUCUCUGAGAUCAUUUGAUCUAACAACAGUAUUUUGCAGAAAUAAUAGCAGGUUUGAGAUGACCUGUACUAUCUGUCUAAUCUGAAGAUGAGCAACAGAGGCUCAGAGAGGCUAAGUGACUUAUCUAAGAUGACCCAGCUACUUAGUGGAAUGAAUGAUGUUGUUGAGAAUAGAACCCAGGUUCCUUAUUUUCAUCAAUCUGCACGUGAUGGGCUCUGCAACAUCAUUAGGUACCAUGGCCAAUAGGCAGAUAGUUUUAGGUGCCCCUUAUAAUAAUGAACUACCAAGAUGCCUACUCUCAGGUUGUUCAGAAUCUAGUUUUGGACUUCUACUGUAUGCCUGGCAUUGUGCUUGAUGCUGGAGUUACAUAGAUGAACAGACAGUGGAUUCUGACCCCAGGAGCUCACAGGAGACUGAAAUACAAGGAAAGGAAUAUAUUACUACGCUAGGGCUUACUGACCCAUGGAGCAUCUGAAACUGGUCCAAUUUUCCCAUAGAACUGAUGUUUAUUGCUUCUUUUGAAUAAACAUAGAAAACUUAAGAAACUUCCAUUUGUGUUAUCUGAGUUCCUUUCUCAGAAAACCAACCCUCAGGUCUCCCAGAUAUUAUCAAGGAGCUGAAACUUAACCAGAUCACCAAGUCUGAGCAAACCCCAGACCAUUCAUCCAUCGUAAUUGCCUAAGUGACCACCUGCUUCCUGUUGGCCAACUCCCCUUCCUUACCCCUCCCUAAUUCCUGUUUUCCGAUGUGUACUUAUAUUCCUUCCCUGCUAUAUAAACCCCUAAUUUUAGUGGGUCAGGGAGAUGCCGUGUGAUUAAAACCUUCUUCCCUUGCAAUACGCGUUUUCUCUGAGAUCGACUUUCUGUGCUGUGAGCAGCAGGACCUGGACAUGACCCCCUGGCAUUUCAGUCACAGAUAUUCCCUGGGGAUGGUGAGCCCUCACUGCGUACUUCAAGGCAGAGGGAUGUAUUUUUAUUUCCUGUUUAUUUUACAACAUCAGAAAUGGAAAUGGUGGCAAAAAGCUUCAUGAAUCAAAUGGACUCUAAAUGACCUUAGCUUCAUCUGUGCACAUCCAGCUAGUGAAUUAAAGUUUGAAAUCCUUUUUUCUCUGUACUUCAAAUCUAUGAUCUUCCUGGAAACACUUGGUAAGAUUAGUUCUGAGGAGUUUCUUUAGGGGCACAAGUGAAAAAUUGGAUUGUAUGCCUUGAUUUGAUAAUUUACACAUUGUGAGCAUGUAUCAAAAACCAAAUGUACCCCAUAAGUAUGUACAAUUAUUAUGUAUCAAAAGUGGGAUUGUAUGUACCCAAAGAGAGAUAAGAUGUGGAUAUGGGUAUCAUUGUAUCUAAGUCAAGGGGUGAAUAGUUGGUUUUUCAGUUAAAUUAAGGCUCGUUUUUCUUCUGGUAAUCUGGAAAUGGCAGCAGAUUAGGAAGUUUUACUAUGUGCUAAACCCUAUUUGAAGUAUUUUAUUUGUAGAAUUUAUUUUUUCAACACAUACAAAAAUACUUGAAGAACUGAGAUUCACAUCGAUGGAAUACUUCGGGUCAGACGACUAUGACAGGCUGAACCAGCAUUGGAACAAAUGUCUGUCUGUCUCUAAAGCUUUUACUCCCAAGAUUGCUAUGGUACCUUUAUGGGUACCAAGAGUAAUACGUUACGUGGCAGUGGAUGUUUUAGCUGUGUUUACAUUGUAUUUGGACCAAAUUAUAGACUCCUGGAGUAUAGGGACCAUAGUUUACACAAUUUUAUAAUGUCUUCCCAAAAGUGUGGCAAGUAUAGUACAGUGUGUAGACACAGAAGGUUCUUGAUAAAGGUGUAUGGAAAGAGUAAAUGUAGCAAUUUAAUAGUCAACAUGGUGAGUAAAAACUGUGUUCGUGAAUAGACAAAUCACAUUCAAGGAUCCCCAUAUUUGAGUGUAAAUCUGACCUUGGAGAAACCAAACAGAAAACUCACCUUUAGAAAUCUCUUUUAUUAUAAUUUUCAGUUUAUAAGCAUGCCUGUUUUCAACUAUAUUCCUACAUACUAUGUGUUUUCUUAAAAGUUACCUAUAAAUAAAUUAUAUAUUCAUACUCUUGUGGCAGGCUGGCUGGAUUUAAUAGGGGCAGGAAGGCUUCCAACAUGUUACGUGUUCUUGAAGGUAAUAAAAAGGAGGACUAAUUACCUAGCUGAAACGAUUAUAAGGGACGUGUUGGACAUCUGGACUCUCUGGGAUUCUGACAUCAGCAAAAGUGGUUAAGAAAAUAUGGUUUUUGAGAAACAGCAAAGACCAUCUAUUUGAACCAAGUUGUUUUAUUCAAUCUAUGACGUGGGUGUAUCUGUGGUCCGCUGAGCAUGAGGACAGGACUAAAUAAUGCAUUGAGCUUCUGUGGUUGAAGUGGCAAUUUUAAAGAACGUGGCUGGUGUUCACAGUUGGAGUCUGUGAGGUCUUACUUUUAAUGAUUAUACCUUUCCCGUAGCCAUCUGUCUUUCUUUUUAAUAAGCAAUACUCCUUAUCGAGCCUGAUUUGUGCACAUUGAUUGCACCAUUAUACUUGUUAAAUAUUAAAGAGUUUUUUUUCUCGUGUGAAGUCUAAUUAGGCAAAGUAUUCAGGGCAAGCCUGGCAUUACCAUUCAGAAUAAUAGUCUGGUCAUAACAUACCUCAGCUUUCUGGAUCAUUUGUCUUUUUUUUUCCUUUCUUAUUAGAGUGCCAGUGUAGCAAAUAUAUUGCAUAAAAAUUUGAUGAAGGAUUCAGUGCUAUUGGGCCAUUAAGAGAAAUUAUGCUACAAAGAUUAUGAAACCUCUAAAAAAUGUGUGGAGAAAUUUAUCAUCUAUAGUUUGCAUUUUUUAUGAAUCAGACUUCUGAAAAGAUAUAUAGAAUAGUUACUUGAUGGCAUUAAUUUUAUUCAAUGGAGCCAUCUUAAAGUUGCUUUAAAUCAUAAAAAUAUAAAUUACAAUGAUGUUGGGAAGAAGAAAAUAGCAAUCAAUAAGUAGUUACAUUUUAUACAUGCUGAUGAUGAAAAGAGUAUUUUUAGAUAUCAAACCACCAUCACUGAAAGUCCAUGUGGUGAACCCUUACUUACUUUCUCAACUUAUCUGUUCUGUGCAGUCUAAUUCAAAAGUAUAUUCGCAUCGCUGAUUUAGCUGCAAGUAUUUUGUCUGUAUAGGGCCAAAAGUAAGAUUAUGACUCACUCUAGUAUCUUUGAUAAGUUAUCUGAUAUCAUUUUGAGAUGAUCAUCAUAAUGAAUAUGGUCCUUUCUUGAGAUGUUCAUAGUACUUUCUCAUUUGUGCACACACACUCAGGCAUACACAUACACAUGUAAUCUGGGCUGACUGUCAUGAACCACAUUAGGAAUAGGACCAGUUUAUUGCUGCGUACUCUCAGGAAUAAAAGCUUCCACUCCAUACGUUUCAUGUAAUGUAUGGUUAUCGGACUAAUAGAUUUUUCCCUCUCAGUGGUUCCAGCAGCUCAUGUUGGGGUUUUGAAAGUGGCUUUAUCCCUUCACAAUUGCAAAUAGCAACAGUGUUCCUUUCCAUUUAUGCAUUAUGGAAAUCAGCGUGUGUGUAUCUCCCUAAAGUGAGAGUUUAUUGUGAGUUGUUUUUGAAUGUGGUCAAAUCAAAAUGAGAUCUGGCUCUGAAUGAAAACAGGGAAAUAAAGAUCAAACAAGGGAAGGGAAUGUAUAGAUCAUCUAGUCCAGUGUUUCUGCACCACAGAAGGAGAAGCCAAAGCUCAGAGAGGCAAAGAGGCUUCUCAGAGUUCACGUGGUUGCCAGUGGCAGAAGUGGAACAGGAGCUAGGCUCAUUCCCUGUGCAUUUUCUACAGUACAGUGGAGGCCCCUGAUAGACGAUGACAUUUGGACCAUUUCCCAGUUUCCAGACCCUUCACAGAUAUAAUGUAUUUUGGCCUGUAGGUUAGAAAGAUGUUGAAGGAAGGAUAGUUGCCUACGGCCUGCUGAAGACAGGGUUGGGAUCAUCUGCAUCUGUCUAGGGUGAUAUUUUUUCAUUGGCAUAUUGUUAGAAGCUGAAAUCUCAAUGAUGAAAAUUCCCAGGGCAGCCUUUGAGAAUUUCAGGGUUCAGUAGCUAGUCAGAGAGGGCAGCAAACAGCUGUCGUGGGGGAUGCAUUGGCUGCAGCUGGGCCAGACCAGGUCUCAGCGGAGGAGUUGGGUGUUCUGUUUCAGAGGCCUGGCAUCUUGCAUAUUCAGCCUGCAAGGGCAGUGAUCAGGUCUUAAGUAAAUCACCUAGCCAAGAGAGGCCCCACGGUUGAAAAGGACCCAAGAGAUAAACAGGUUAAUUUACCUUUGUAGGUAACUGUCACGGCAACUUGAAUAUUCAGUUUAUACGGCACUGUGGUUUGGCACAUUGGGUCUGAAGUCUAAGAUGUCUGGGUUAGACCAGCUGCCAUUUACUAGCUGUGGAAUUUUGGCAAGUUACUUUACCACUUUGAGCCUCAGUUGUUUUGUCUAUAAAAUGGGAAUGAUAGCAAACAUUUAUAUUGUGCUCACUGUGUGCCAAGCGCUGUCUCAGUUGUUUUGUCUGUAAAAUGGGCAUUAUAACAUUUAUAUUUUGCCUAGUGUAUGCCAGUUGCUUUAGGAGAAAACCCUGUGAGGCAGGCACUACCAUUAUCCUCUCUUUAUAGUGAGGAAACUGAGGCCCAAAGGGGCUUAAUGUCUUGCUCAAGGUUACGCAGCUGUUCAGGGUUGAGCAGGGAUUUGAAUCUUGGCAGUCUGUUGCUUUUUAUCACUUUCCUAUGCGGCCUGUUGAUAGGAUUAAGAUUAUUGUGAGGAUCGAAUGGGAUAAGCACACCAGAAAUAUUAGCUCUCAUCAUUAUUAAUUAUAAUAAAGCUAGCAUUACCUUAAUAACAAGAAUAAAAUCCAUAUGAUCAGCCGUUUCUUUUCCUGUAGACAAGUUCCUUAAGUAAGAAGCCAGAUCAUAAUUAGAAAGUUGCUUUGGCAAUUACUGAAGUAAUGUGAAAAGAAUUCAGAAGCCUUUAUUAAAUGUCCCUAUAGUUCAUGGAGCCUUGGUCUAGCCGAGUAGACUGCCAGCAGGAUCAGCUCCCCGACUCUUUUGGCUAAGACUCCCUUUUUUUUUUUUUUUUUUUGAUGGAGUCUCACUCUUUCGCCCAGGCUGGAAUUCAGUGGUGCAAUCUCGGCUCACUGCAACCUCCGCUUCCCGGCUUCAAGCGAUUCUUCUGACUCAGCCUCCAGAGUAGCUGGAAUUACAGGUGUGUGCCACCACGCCCGGCUAAUUUUUGUAUUUUUAGUAGAGACGGGAUUUCACCAUCUUGGCUGGGCUGGUCUCAAACUCCUGACCUCGUGAUCCAUCCGCCUCAGCCUGCCAAAGUGCUGGAAUUACAGGCGUAAGCCACUGUGCCCGGCUAAGACUCCCUUUUCACCUCUGAGGGCUUGCAGACUUUUCCUACUAUAGGGAGCUCUGGAGUACCAGUGACCAACUCUGUGAUGGUUUUCUCUGAUCUAUCCAUGCAGAUGAUUAAAGUAGAUUAGAUAGGUUAUGGGCAUUGUCUGUGCCACUGGACUGCCACUGUAGAAUUGUCUAAGAACAACACCCCAGUCUUGGAGGAAAUCCUUCAACCUACGCACAAAAGUCAGUUUUUGACUUGCUUCCUCCAUUUUGUUGAGUUCAUGACCUCAUUCUCAGAGUGUGAUCUUAUUUCCAAGUUGCUUUGCUAUGGAGUUUAGAUAUUAUCUUGUGUCUCUUCUUUUGCUUAGUUUUAAAUUUAUAAAUUGUGAAUACAUAUGUGGGUAUGUAACAUGUGCAUCCAUUUUAACUUAUGAUAAUAAAGCAAAUAACUAUCCAUAAGCAUCUAGAACAUUCCUUUGAAACCCUUCACAUGUGCUUCCUGGUCAUAUUUCCUUCCUACCUCCCACUCCCUCACCCCAGGGGUAACUGCUUUUUCAAAUAUUGUUAACUAUUUCCUUCCUUUUCUUUCAAGCUUUACCAGAAAUGUGCAUCCACAAAUAAUUUGUUUUUGUUCCAGUUCAACAGGCUGUUGAAUGGGAAAAUUUGACUAACCCUUCAAGAUAUAUUAUAUAACAGUUACUAAAAUAAGUUGCAAGAAAGACCCCAGUGGAAUUUUUCAAAUGAAAUAUCCAAACACCAGGCUCAAGCUCUUGAAAAUCCUCCUCACUCUGAAGAUACAGUAAAACACUGGUACUGGAUGUGUGAGGGGAUUUAUUUGAAGAAGCCUCUGCUGUGCGCCCGUCACUGUCCUUUCAUCCUGGAGGAAGGGUUGUGGGGGUGCUGCCCCCACCCCAAGCCUAGAGAGAGCAGCUGCUUUGAGGCUGCCUGGACAGCAGACUCUGUGUCCCUUGGGACUUGGAGUGUGGCAGGCUGUCAUGUGACUCGGGUGAGACACUUUGGUGGCAGAGUGAAGGGGAGCAGCUGGGAUAGGGCCUCCCCGCUGCCAAGCGUGUUGGAGAGAUUUGUGUGUGCUUCCUGUGGACCAGAUGUGGCCCAGGUGGGAUGGAGAGCCAGGCUGGAACAAUUUGGCCUCUGCCCAGGAGGCACAGGCAGCGGAGAGCUUGUGGAGUGAAUUUUAGGGGCUGCAGGGGUAGGGUUGGGGGCAGUACAAACAGAAGACUUAAAUGCAUCAUCCACAUCACAGGGAUUUUGGUUAAAGGGGCCCAGCAGGGAGCCCCUGGAAAACCUACAAAAGUACCCAUAAGAAAGAGAGAACAUUGGUUUGAGUAUCUGCUGGUCUACAGGAUGUGAAGCCAUUUGCACUAGUGAGGAUUAAGUUUCCCUGCAUAUAAAUGAAAGAACAACGGUAACACAAAAUAGGAGUUUACUUCUUUCUUACAUAGAAUAAGUCAAGAAGUAGGCAAUUUGGGAAUGGGGUGGUGGUUCCACACAGUUAUUAGGAACAAGUCUUCUACUUCACUGCUCCCACAUCCUAGGAAUAGAUUCCUCGUGCUCAUGGCGCAAGAGAGCUGCUAAAGCUCCAGCCAUCACAUCACGUUCCAGGCAUAGAAGGAAAGGAAGGGCAGAGGAACGGUCUGCCCCCUCCUAUUUAAGGAGACUUUUGGGAUGCCCCACCUAACAUUUUUGCUUAUUAGCCAGGGUUCACUUGUGUGGUCAUGCCUAGCUCUAAGAGAAGCCAGGAAAUAUAAACUUAUUGCUGUGAUUCUUUUUGUGAAGAGGAAGGGGAUAUAGUGAGGCAGCCAGCAUUUUCAUGGCAGUGGCAGUCAUGUGGUCUUUCUUCAUCAUGUGUUUCAAACCCAGAGAGAAGAGUAACAGCAGCUAAAAGGUGGGUAGAAAAGAGAGAAGAAGCCUACAGGCUACCUGUACAGAUCCUAGCUGGGGAUGCAGCAGGAAGUCUUACUGUUUGUUUGAUCUUCUUUAGAGUCAAUGUCAUACAUUGACUUGAACGUUCUAUUUUCUGAAUCACAAUUAUUUUUUGUGACUUAAAAGUAACUUUAGGACUUUCUGUUACCUACAAGUGGCCAGAAAAUUACAGGGCCUACUAGAUUUUUCCUUGAGUAGCACGAUAGAAGCAUACCCCCUAAAUAUCAUAUAUAUUUCAACUUGAUAAGGUCUUUAUUGUACAUAACCACCAUGCUGUUUUCAUACCUAAAAAUUAUCAUUCUUUAAAAAUUACUGAAUACCCAGACCAUGUUUAAAUUGUCCUUAUCUCAAAAAGUAUCUCUUUUUGUUUGAUUAAUGUUGUAUAGGAGGGCCUCACAUUGCAUUUGAUUGUUUAGUCUCUGAAGUCUCUUGUAAUUGAAAGUCCUCUUCCUCAUAUUGUCAUUUACUUGUUUUGUGUCUUCUAUAUUUUCUAUCAACGUUACUUAUAUCUAGAGGUUUAAUUAAAUGGAGGUUCAUUUUUUUCAGACAAAAAUAAUUCAUAGUUUAUAUGAAUAAUUAUUUUUGCUCCUAUCGCUGCACAGUGUCUUAUGGUUCUGCUUUUAGUGAUGCUUGGCCAGCCCUUAACUUUAAAACUUCCUUAUGUUUUUAUUUUGUGUAUUUGUGUCUUAAAAUUUUUUUAUCAUGGUAAAAUAUACAUAGUAUAAAAUUCAUUAUUUUUACCAUUUUUAGGUGAACAUUUCAGUGGCAUUAAGUGCAUUCAUGUUGUUAUGUAACCAUCACGAAUGUUCAUCUCCUGAACUUUUUUCAUGUCUCCAAACUGAAACUCAUACCUAUUUAACUAUAAUUCCUCAUUCCUUCAUCCUCCAGCCCCUGACAACCACCAUUCUACCUUCUGUCUGUAUAAAUUUGACCAAUUUAAGAACUUCAUAUACAUGGAAUCAUAUAGUGAUUUGUCCUUUUGUGAAUGGUUUAUUUCACUUACUGUAAUGUCUUCAAGGUUCAUCCAUGUUGUAGCAUGCGUCAGAAUUUUCUUUCUUUUUAAAGCAGAAUAAUAUUCCACUCUAUGUCUUGCUUUCUUAUUUCCCCAUUAGGAAAAAUAUGUUUUUCUUUAUGGAGAUGAGAUCCUGCUCUGUCACUCAGGAGUACAGUAGUGUGAUCAUAGCUCACUGCAGCCUCGAAUUCUUGGGCUCAAGUGAUCCUCUUGCUUCAGCCUCUCGAGUAGCUGAGAAUUACAGGUGCAAACCAUGGCGCCUGGCUACUUCAUUUUUUAUUGUUGCAAAAUACACAUAACAAAAUUUAUCAUCUUAACCAUUUUUAAGUGUACAGUUCAUUGGUAAUAAAUACAUUCAUGUUAUGCAACUAUCACCACUGCCCAUCUCCAGAACUCUUUUAAUAUUGUCAAACUGAAACUCUGUAUCCAUUAAACAAUUAACUGUGUGUUUAUCCAUCUCCUAGCCCCUGGCAUUCUACUUUCUGUCUUUAUGAUUUUGACCACUCUAAGUACCUCAUAUAAGUAGAAUCAUAAUAUUUUGUGUAUCCUUUUAUUUUGAAGUGAAAAUAGCAUUUAGCUAGAUUUAGAACUAUCUAUGUGAUGAUCUCAGUCUUUAAGUUAGAGCCUUAGUACAUUUACAUUUAUUGUGAUUACUGCUACUUAUGUGCCUUAUUUAUUCUACUUCUUUUAUGUUUCAUUUUCUCUCCUUCUUUUCCUUCCUUUGAAUUGAGUGCUUUUUUUUUCUUUUUCCAAUUUUUUUCUUCUACUGGUUUGGAAGUUACACAUUCUAUUGUUUUUCCAGUUGUUCUCUUAGAAAUUUUUCCGUAUGUGUGUAACUUAACAAAGUCUACAAUUAACCACUAAUCAAUAUAUUUAUGUUUCUUUUUCCUAAAAGAAAGUAUUAGAAAACUGUGAUCCCCACCUGUUUAGUAUUUUUGCCUUAUCUAUCUUGUAAAUUGACAAAUUAGAUAUUAUUGCUAUUGUACUAAAUGGUGAGCAUUCAUUUGGGUUUAACCCCAUUUAUGUAUUUUUUUUUCCCAGUCACAGUUUCUUCUUGCCUCCUAGACUCUUUCUGGGAGAUAUAUACUUCCCGAAAUACAUUAUUUAGAAGUUCUUUUAGUAAGGGCCUGUUGGAAGUAAACUCUCCUAGUUUUAUUUAUCUGACAGUAACUUCAUUUUAUUCUAAGCUUUCAAAGAUAGUUUCAUUAGGUGUAAAAUUCUAGGUUGGAAGUUAUUAACUUUCAGUACUUAAAAUAUAGUAUUUAACUGGCUUUUGAGAAGUCAGUUUUAAAUUGAAUUGAUAUUUAUAGAAACAUGCCUUUUUUAUCUGGCUGCUUUAAAUAUCUUUGUUUUUCCUAUCUCUACUCUCUCCUUUCUGCUUUUAUUUUUAAUGUGGUGAGUGAGGAUUUUUUUUUUAUCCUGUUCAGAGUUUUGUGAGAUUCCUGAACUCAAGGAUAAUUGUCUUUCAUCAAUCUUGGAAAAUUCUCAGCCAUUAUUUCUUUGAAAAUAACCUCUUUCCCCAAUGUUUCUGGUGUUUCCUUCUGGAACUCUAGUGAGAUGUGCUGUAGAGUUCCUCUCUGUUCCUUAAAUCUAGUUCAUAUUUCUAUCUUUUUUCUCCCUCUGUGCUGUUCGCUGGGUAAUUUUUUCAGCUCUAUUUUCUGUUUUACAAAUUCUCUUUUUAACCAUGUCCAAUACAACAUGUAGACCAUCUAUUCGGUUUCUAAUGUCAACGUACAGACAUACUGUGCGUAAGAACUGUUCAGUUAAUGGCUUUUUGAAAAGUAAUGCCACUCUUUGGAUGAUUCCUGGUUUUAUUUUUUUUUUUUUUGGUUUUGGGACCUAAUGACUUUCUCAGUCCCAAGCACAUGAGAUAAAACCCUAUAGGAAGUGAUAUUUAGACAUUAGAAAUUCAGGAAAAGACAUAGUCAGCAGUGUGUGAGAGACUAUCCUAUAGAAACUUUUUCUGUAAAGGGCUGGAUAAUAAAUAAAUAUUUUAGGCUAUUGUGGGCCAUUCAGUGUAAGUUACAACUACUCAAGUCUGUCGUCAUAGGAAAAAAGCAGCCAUAGACUACAAGUAAAUGAAUGAUAUUCUAAUAAAACUUUAUUUAUAAAAACAAGCGGGCUAUAGUUUUCUGACCCCUGCUAAGGAAAUUUGAAUUCUGCUUUGUGUUGGGAUGAAUUAAAACAUUUGCUGUGCACACAUUGCAAACAAAAGACAAGAAGAGAUGGCUGUUGUACAUCUCUUUAGUUUGUUGUGAUCGCACUAUUUCCGUAAGUUUUGAAGCAUUUUUUUGCCUUAAAUGUGUUUUCCUGUGUUGCAAUAUUAUUUUUACAUGCAGAUUGAAUGUGAAAUACCCAUAAACUUACCAAAUGUUGAAAAUUGAUAAAACACAUUGAUAAAAUUGAUUGUAUAAAAAGAAGAAAAAAGCCUUUAUGUACUUUGUAUUUUUUCUAUGCUAUAUAUUUGUUCACUUUUGAAUUGUUUUUAGGAUUUGAAUUUGUUUUUAAUGUUCAAUUGACAUAUUAUUCUACCUGUCAAGGUUGUCUGGAUGUCUUCCAUGGAGAUAGAAUGUAUUAUAAUUUUUCUCCAUUGAAGUUAUUGGAACUAUUUUUAUAUUUAACAAUUUUUCAUGUAAAGUUGUUAAAUAAGGGUCAGAUCUUCUGUCUUUCAAUACAUAAAAUUUUAUUUUUUUAAGUCUAUCUGAUAGUUCUUCAUAGUCUCUUUGUCUUUUGCCAUACACUUAAAGAUAAAACAUUUUUAUAGUUUUUCUUUGAUAGUUCCAAUAUCUGCAAUUUUUGUGCAUGUAAUUUUGCAGCAUGGUUUUUUUUCUGUUACUUGCUCAUGACAGCUUUCCCUCCUGAGAAUUUUGUGGUAUUUUGAUUUGAGCUUAUGGUCAUUGGAAUGUUAUCUGUGGGAAUGUUAAUGUGAGAAUUUUUUGAGGCCUAUAUUUAAAGUGUAUUUGUUCAGAGAGGACUUAUAUUUAUUUCUUGGAGGCAUCUGGGAGUACUGUCAUUCCAAGGUGUUUCAAAAUGAAAUCUUUGAUAUGGAAAUUUUGGGGCCCCAGAGUGCCAAUUUCAGCCUAUACCUGUGUGAAGGAGGCCUUAUAUAUAUUAGGCAUUCUCAGGGCACCUCUUUUUCAUUUUUCACCCAGAGCCAAUGCUGAGAUGGGCAAGCAUCUCCACUUGCUUUCUUGAAUCAUAUUUUUCUAAUUUACCUCCUAAGGCUGCUGCAUUUUGGGGGUUCUCAGUUCUGUGCAUGGGAUCUCUUCUGGCACUCUGGCCCCAGCAUAUGCCCUAGACAUUGCCCCUUGUCCCUUCUAAGUGGCUCACUACCAUUGAUUUCCUGGAUAGCAAGAUCAAACCUGAUCUUUCUUAUCUGUUUGGAUCCAUGCUUUCCUGUUAUUUCAGGGCUCUGACAGUUUUCCUUAUUUACCCAUCAUCUCAACCGUGCAUUCAGAUAUACAUUUAUAAUGUAUAUGUAUAUUUAUAAUAUACAUACACACAUAUAUACAUAUACACAUAUAUGUAUAUAUUAUGUGCGUGUUUUGACAUUCAGUAACUUUAUGUAUUUUGUACAGGUUUUCUUCAGCUAUCCGGUCUGCCAUAUUACUGGCAAUGGAAGUCUGUGUUUUCUUCUUCCUCAGAUUUUUCUGUGACCUCUCAGACAUUCAGCCAAGAGUCAACACUAAUAGAAGAAGAGAAGAGUACUUCAGAAUUCUUCUCUUUCUUGUGUUAAAAGAAAAACUUCAGACAAGUUAAAUUUAGUGGAGUUUAUUUGUGCAAAGAAUAAUUCAUGAACCAGGCAGCACCUUGAAGUAGUAGAGGUUCAGAGAGCUCAGCCCAGCAAUGUGCGCAGGCAAUAUAUAUGGACAGAGAAAGGAAGUAUAGGCACAGCUUGAUUAGUCAUGGCUGGGCAUUUGUCUUAUUUGGGUGCAAUAUCAUGAGGCAUUUACCUUAUGAUCUGAUUCAUUGGCAGCCUGUGAUUGGCUGAAGCUUGGCUGCUGUGAUUGGCUGAGACUCAGCUUUUUGUUACAAGAAUAUUCUCUUAAGUUAUGUGGCAGUUUGCUGUGUAAGGAUUCAAAGUAUUGAAGCAGAUUUAGGCCAACUUCAUCCAGUUUAACACUUGGUACAAGGUGUAGAUUUCAGGUUGUGUACAGGAGGCUGAUACUUUGAAAUUUUUUAUCUCUGAUUCACAUACCUUGAUUCUGAGAUGGAAGUGAUAUGGGGAGUGGCCAUUCAGGUUCUGUUAUAAUUCCCAGAGCCUGGCACUAGCCUGGUCCCUCUCCAUCCCUUGAUUGAGGAGCCUCAGCGUUCAUUGUUGGGGGGUGAACAGAUAGCCCUGGCUCCCUGGUGUGCCAUGAAGCAGCUGGGUACACUUCUUAGAGUGCAUUCUGGCCUCCUCUAUGGUUUGGGCUUGCACUCCUGGGCUUGGUCAUGAAUUCUAAGCUGGAGAUAAGCUGUUCCUUCCUUUUCAGUAUUCAGGGAUGGCAGCAGAGGUUCCCUUCUGGCUACUUUCAUGUACAAUACGGAAAAAAAAAGGGCCUUAAUGACAACAAAUAAAACUCAUAUGAGCAGAAGCAAAAUGUAGAAUUCUCACCUUAGCUAGUCUGCCUUGGGAAAGGUCAGUGCACAUGUAGACGUCUUUCAGGCAAAGAGAAAAGCAUGCAUAAUUUAGCACGGGCAUUCUUUUAGCAGCAGAAGGACAUAGACCACUCGGCACACAGAGUGCAUUGUGCAUUGCCUUUGUUACCCUCUGAUUAAAAUUCUGUCUUAGCAGUUGUGGAGGAGGUGAGCGAUAAUCCAUAUUGGCGUAAAACUUCAUAUGUCACACAGCUGCUGGCUCCUAACUCAGAAAGUUUGAGACAAUGGUGUUGAUUUGGUAGUUAUCCUGCAUAGGGAAUUGAUUUAUUCUUACUAAUAGAAAAUAUAGGUUUUUGAAGUAGGCAAUAAUGGAAUCUCUUUUAUGCUUAAAUAGAAUUCCACAUUAAUAAUUGGUGGAGUGUGGGCCUUGGCUGUGAUCUUGCAAUGUGAACAUACCACAAGGAGCAAGUUCCAAAUUGACAAGAGUGCUUUAUAAAAUGUGAACUUGGAAUAUAGGGAUGGGAUUUUAUUCUUAUUUAACUCAUAUUUCUGAGAUACCUUCCAUAUAAAGCACUGCUAUGUAAAACAAAAGAAACAGAAAACAAUAUUUUGUUACAUUGAUACUGAUUGUUCUUUUCACUUCUGUCCAGAAGUUCUACUCUUUAUCAAAUUAUUUAUUAAUCCUCAGAAAUCCUCUUUCAGCACUGUACCAUUUCUAAUAUAACAGGGUAAAGGGAUGAGUUAGUAGUAUAAUCCUUUGAAAUUAUAAGUACUCCAUUUUUCACCAUUUAUAUUUUAUUCCCUUUGUAUUGCAAAAUAAAUUUGAGACAUUGACAUGUUCUACUUUUAAAAAGAACAAAUCAAGAACAACAUAUCCAUUAUCAUCAAAGUUACAAAAUAGAUAAAUUAGAAAAUUAUUUGCAUUCUAAAAAACCACAACAACAAUUAAACUGCCCUUUGUAGGAUGCAGCAAUGCAAAGUAAUACAGAGGGUGAUUCAUAUGGCAAGGGAAUGGAUUUUGAAAUGACGUAAUUUAUAAAGAUCCAUAUAUGUAACUUUUCUGCAACUUGAUCUAUUGCCUAAAGUGUCUGUGGAUACUUCUCACUUCUCUGUAUGUUGUUUUAACUCAUAAACCUUGAUGCUGUUUUCCUGUUUAUUUUUUUAACACAUACUCAUCGAGCCACUACCAUGUGCCAGGUGCUGUGCUGGUGAUAUGGGGUGAAAGUCCCAUGAAGACACAUAUAUGGCUGCUUUUUAUUCUAUUUUCAGGAUCAGGGAAGACAAUAUCAAGUGAAAGGUCAACUAUCGUCUUAGGUAUGUCUUUAUCAGCAGCAUAAAAACGGACUAAUACAAGUACACAAGAAUACAAAGAAAAGAACAGCAGACACUGGGGCCCACUUGAGGGUAGAGGAUGGAAGGAGGAUGUGGAUCAAAAGCCUACUUAUCAGCUGCCUUCCUAUUUCAAGGAAAGACGCCAAGGUAAUUUUGACCCAGAGGAGCAAUGAUGUAGCCACCUCCUAACCUUCCCUUCUUGAACCCCCAGAAGUUAUGCCAGGAUUUACUAGAGAGUGUCAACUCAACCAGCAAGCGGCUCCUUCGGCUUAACUUGUGGUUGGAGGAGAGAACCUUUGUGGGGCUGCGUUCUCUUAGCAGUGCUCAGAAGUGACUUGCCUGAGGGUGGACCAGAAGAAAGGAAAGGUCCCCUCUUGCUGUUGGCUGCACAUCAGGAAGGCUGUGAUGGGAAUGAAGGUGAAAACUUGGAGAUUUCACUUCAGUCAUUGCUUCUGCCUGCAAGAUCAUCCUUUAAAAGUAGAGAAGCUGCUCUGUGUGGUGGUUAACUCCAAGAGGCAGAACUCGUUCUAGAAGGAAAUGGAUGCAAGCAGCUCCGGGGGCCCCAAACGCAUGCUUCCUGUGGUCUAGCCCAGGGAAGCCCUUCCGUGGGGGCCCCGGCUUUGAGGGAUGCCACCGGUUCUGGACGCAUGGCUGAUUCCUGAAUGAUGAUGGUUCGCCGGGGGCUGCUUGCGUGGAUUUCCCGGGUGGUGGUUUUGCUGGUGCUCCUCUGCUGUGCUAUCUCUGUCCUGUACAUGUUGGCCUGCACCCCAAAAGGUGACGAGGAGCAGCUGGCACUGCCCAGGGCCAACAGCCCCACGGGGAAGGAGGGGUACCAGGCCGUCCUUCAGGAGUGGGAGGAGCAGCACCGCAACUACGUGAGCAGCCUGAAGCGGCAGAUCGCACAGCUCAAGGAGGAGCUGCAGGAGAGGAGUGAGCAGCUCAGGAAUGGGCAGUACCAAGCCAGCGAUGCUGCUGGCCUGGGUCUGGACAGGAGCCCCCCAGAGAAAACCCAGGCCGACCUCCUGGCCUUCCUGCACUCGCAGGUGGACAAGGCAGAGGUGAAUGCUGGCGUCAAGCUGGCCACAGAGUAUGCAGCAGUGCCUUUCGAUAGCUUUACUCUACAGAAGGUGUACCAGCUGGAGACUGGCCUUACCCGCCACCCCGAGGAGAAGCCUGUGAGGAAGGACAAGCGGGAUGAGUUGGUGGAAGCCAUUGAAUCAGCCUUGGAGACCCUGAACAGUCCUGCAGAGAACAGCCCCAAUCACCGUCCUUACACGGCCUCUGAUUUCAUAGAAGGGAUCUACCGAACAGAAAGGGACAAAGGGACAUUGUAUGAGCUCACCUUCAAAGGGGACCACAAACACGAAUUCAAACGGCUCAUCUUAUUUCGACCAUUCGGCCCCAUCAUGAAAGUGAAAAAUGAAAAGCUCAACAUGGCCAACACGCUUAUCAAUGUUAUCGUGCCUCUAGCAAAAAGGGUGGACAAGUUCCGGCAGUUCAUGCAGAAUUUCAGGGAGAUGUGCAUUGAGCAGGAUGGGAGAGUCCAUCUCACUGUUGUUUACUUUGGGAAAGAAGAAAUAAAUGAAGUCAAAGGAAUACUUGAAAACACUUCCAAAGCUGCCAACUUCAGGAACUUUACCUUCAUCCAGCUGAAUGGAGAAUUUUCUCGGGGAAAGGGACUUGAUGUUGGAGCCCGCUUCUGGAAGGGAAGCAACGUCCUUCUCUUUUUCUGUGAUGUGGACAUCUACUUCACAUCUGAAUUCCUCAAUACGUGUAGGCUGAAUACACAGCCAGGGAAGAAGGUAUUUUAUCCAGUUCUUUUCAGUCAGUACAAUCCUGGCAUAAUAUACGGCCACCAUGAUGCAGUCCCUCCCUUGGAACAGCAGCUGGUCAUAAAGAAGGAAACUGGAUUUUGGAGAGACUUUGGAUUUGGGAUGACGUGUCAGUAUCGGUCAGACUUCAUCAAUAUAGGUGGGUUUGAUCUGGACAUCAAAGGCUGGGGCGGAGAGGAUGUGCACCUUUAUCGCAAGUAUCUCCACAGCAACCUCAUAGUGGUACGGACGCCUGUGCGAGGACUCUUCCACCUCUGGCAUGAGAAGCGCUGCAUGGACGAGCUGACCCCCGAGCAGUACAAGAUGUGCAUGCAGUCCAAGGCCAUGAACGAGGCAUCCCACGGCCAGCUGGGCAUGCUGGUGUUCAGGCACGAGAUAGAGGCUCACCUUCGCAAACAGAAACAGAAGACAAGUAGCAAAAAAACAUGAACUCCCAGAGAAGGAUUGUGGGAGACACUUUUUCUUUCCUUUUGCAAUUACUGAAAGUGGCUGCAACAGAGAAAAGACUUCCAUAAAGGACGACAAAAGAAUUGGACUGAUGGGUCAGAGAUGAGAAAGCCUCCGAUUUCUCUCUGUUGGGCUUUUUACAACAGAAAUCAAAAUCUCCGCUUUGCCUGCAAAAGUAACCCAGUUGCACCCUGUGAAGUGUCUGACAAAGGCAGAAUGCUUGUGAGAUUAUAAGCCUAAUGGUGUGGAGGUUUUGAUGGUGUUUACAACACACUGAGACCUGUUGUUUUGUGUGCUCAUUGAAAUAUUCAUGAUUUAAGAGCAGUUUUGUAAAAAAUUCAUUAGCAUGAAAGGCAAGCAUAUUUCUCCUCAUAUGAAUGAGCCUAUCAGCAGGGCUCUAGUUUCUAGGAAUGCUAAAAUAUCAGAAGGCAGGAGAGGAGAUAGGCUUAUUAUGAUACUAGUGAGUACAUUAAGUAAAAUAAAAUGGACCAGAAAAGAAAAGAAACCAUAAAUAUCGUGUCAUAUUUUCCCCAAGAUUAACCAAAAAUAAUCUGCUUAUCUUUUUGGUUGUCCUUUUAACUGUCUCCGUUUUUUUCUUUUAUUUAAAAAUGCACUUUUUUUCCCUUGUGAGUUAUAGUCUGCUUAUUUAAUUACCACUUUGCAAGCCUUACAAGAGAGCACAAGUUGGCCUACAUUUUUAUAUUUUUUAAGAAGAUACUUUGAGAUGCAUUAUGAGAACUUUCAGUUCAAAGCAUCAAAUUGAUGCCAUAUCCAAGGACAUGCCAAAUGCUGAUUCUGUCAGGCACUGAAUGUCAGGCAUUGAGACAUAGGGAAGGAAUGGUUUGUACUAAUACAGACGUACAGAUACUUUCUCUGAAGAGUAUUUUCGAAGAGGAGCAACUGAACACUGGAGGAAAAGAAAAUGACACUUUCUGCUUUACAGAAAAGGAAACUCAUUCAGACUGGUGAUAUCGUGAUGUACCUAAAAGUCAGAAACCACAUUUUCUCCUCAGAAGUAGGGACCGCUUUCUUACCUGUUUAAAUAAACCAAAGUAUACCGUGUGAACCAAACAAUCUCUUUUCAAAACAGGGUGCUCCUCCUGGCUUCUGGCUUCCAUAAGAAGAAAUGGAGAAAAAAAUAUAUAUAUAUAUAUUGUGAAAGAUCAAUCCAUCUGCCAGAAUCUAGUGGGAUGGAAGUUUUUGCUACAUGUUAUCCACCCCAGGCCAGGUGGAAGUAACUGAAUUAUUUUUUAAAUUAAGCAGUUCUACUCGAUCACCAAGAUGCUUCUGAAAAUUGCAUUUUAUUACCAUUUCAAACUAUUUUUUAAAAAUAAAUACAGUUAACAUAGAGUGGUUUCUUCAUUCAUGUGAAAAUUAUUAGCCAGCACCAGAUGCAUGAGCUAAUUAUCUCUUUGAGUCCUUGCUUCUGUUUGCUCACAGUAAACUCAUUGUUUAAAAGCUUCAAGAACAUUCAAGCUGUUGGUGUGUUAAAAAAUGCAUUGUAUUGAUUUGUACUGGUAGUUUAUGAAAUUUAAUUAAAACACAGGCCAUGAAUGGAAGGUGGUAUUGCACAGCUAAUAAAAUAUGAUUUGUGGAUAUGA